AUGUGUGCUCUAAAGGGUUUUCUGGAAGAAAACUUUUAUACCUACUCAGUGGCCAAAGGCAAUCAUUCAACAGUGUAUGAAUUUAUCCUCUUGGGGCUCACAGAUAAUGCAGAGCUUCAAGUCACUCUCUUUGGUAUAUUCCUUGUAGUAUACUUAGCUAGCUUUAUGGGUAAUUUCGGUUUGAUUAUGCUAAUUCAAAUCAGUCCUCAGCUUCAUACACCCAUGUAUUUUUUCCUCAGCCAUCUGGCUUUUGUUGAUUUUUCUUUUACUUCAUCUGUUGCCCCAAAUACCUUGGUAAAUUUUCUGUGUGAAGUUAAAAGUAUAACAUUUUAUGCAUGUGCCAUUCAGGUAUGCUGCUUCAUCACAUUUGUAGUUUGUGAAUUAUAUUUGCUCUCAAUCAUGGCAUAUGAUCGGUAUGUUGCCAUCUGUAACCCUUUACUUUAUGUCAUUCUCAUUCCUAGAAAACUCUGUAUUAAACUGAUUGCUAGCACGUAUGUGUAUGGAUUCACUGUGGGACUUGUACAGACAGUGGCGACAUCCUACUUGUCUUUUUGUGAUUCCAACGUGAUCAACCACUUCUACCAUGAUGAUGUUCCAUUAGUGGCUCUGGCCUGUUCUGACACUCAUGUCAAAGAGCUGAUGUUGUUAAUCAUUGCUGGGUUCAAUACUCUCUGCUCUCUAGUAAUUGUGCUGAUUUCUUAUGGUUUCAUUUUCUUUGCCAUCCUGAGGAUACAUUCUGCUGAAGGGAGACAGAAAGCAUUUUCUACCAGUGCUUCCCAUCUGACCUCCAUCACAAUAUUUUAUGGAACAAUCAUUUUUAUGUACCCGCAGCCCAAGUCAAGCCAUUCCCUGAAUAUGGAUAAAGUUGCUUCUGUGUUUAAUGUGGUAGUGAUUCCUACAUUAAACCCACUGAUCUAUAGUUUAAGAAAUCAGGAGGUAAAAAAUGCACUAAAGAGAAUUAUAGAAAAGUUAUGUUUGGCUGUCAAAUAA